AGCUUACGGCCGACAAACCACUCUUCUCUAUCAGUAUGCCCUUGAAUAGAUGAGGUUGUGCAAAGUCCUUUGCUCUUAAAUGUAUUGCUGUCAUUGAGAAUAUUUGGAGGUUUUCUCUUGGGUUUGUUUGGAUUUUUUUUUUCAGCUUUUGUCUGAAUUUUGGUUUUAUUUUUCUGGGGCAGAGAAAAUGGCUUUCCUUAUGAAAAGUAUGAUAAGUAACCAGGUAAAGAAUUUAGGAUUUGGUGGUGGGUCUGAAGAAAAUAAAGAAGAAGGAGGUGCAUCUGAUCCUGCAGCAGCUCAAGGGAUGACUAGAGAGGAGUAUGAGGAGUAUCAAAAGCAAAUGAUUGAGGAGAAGAUGGAAAGAGAUGCUGCAUUUACACAGAAAAAGGCAGAAAGGGCAUGCCUCAGAGUUCAUCUCAGAGAAAAAUACAGGCUCCCAAAGAGUGAAAUGGAUGAGAAUCAAAUCCAGAUGGCUGGAGAUGAUGUGGAUUUACCUGAAGAUCUCCGGAAAAUGGUAGAUGAAGAUCAAGAAGAGGAAGAAGAUAAAGAUUCUAUUCUUGGGCAGAUACAGAAUCUCCAGAACAUGGACUUGGAUACCAUAAAAGAAAAAGCCCAGGCCACCUUCACUGAAAUCAAGCAGACAGCGGAGCAGAAGUGUUCCGUGAUGUGAGGGGUGGGAGGGGUGGAGGGAGGGAACCAGCCAUCCUUGGAAAAGACCACUCUCUUGUGGGACGUUUCAAGCAGUACAUGUUUUAAUGUAGUGAACACAGUUAGGAAAACCACGAUGAUCCAUUGACAGACAAUAAUUUGGUUGUUCUAAAUAUUCCUGGCAGAGCAUUUAGCUAACACCUUGCAGCGGGAACCUUACUUUCCUUUUAGUUAUAAAUGAGAUAAACUGGAAAAUUUCAGUUGUAAAUGAUGAUGCAGAACACAUAUCUGCUUAAAGACCUUGAGAUGAGCCAGGAAGAAACAAAAGCAAGGGGCAUUUCCUCUCCAACUUUCUUCCUUGGAGGCCAAGUUCUCACCCUGUCCAACUAUUCGCAGGACACCAGGUCCCUUCAGAGAGAAAUGUGGAGAGUCAAGGUGUCUACUGGGAGCCGGGUUUCCCACAGGGAGCUGAGUCUACAGACUCCAGGGCAAUCAAAGGUCACCACCCCCACCCCUCACCUCUAGGAUCCUUGAAUUUGUCAAUGAUACUCAUCAAGUAUGCUUGGAUCCUUUGGUCCUUGGAUGCUUCUCAGCCAAGUGGCGGUAGCACAGAUGUGGUGAACAAUGACGAAUUGAGGCAGGGAAUAGACCUCACUAGCCCUUUGCAAUGGAGAUCAUCGUUCUAGUGGCCAUGUGAAGAAUGGAACCAAGGGAGGCACAAUUAGAGGCAGAGGGAAACCAGGCAGACGGCUGCUCUUUUUGAGUUGAGCUUAACUCUCCUUGUCUGAACUUGGUGAUAGCAAUGGGAACAAAGUGGGUAGACUAACAGAGAGCAUUAAGAAGUUAAAUCAAUCUCUCUCUGUCUCCUCCCAACCUCUCUCUCUCUUUCAUCCCCUUCUCUCCCUAUCUCUCUUUUUUUUUUCUUCUCCUGUCCCUUCCCAUCCCACCCCUUUAGACUACCUUCCAGUAAAUCACACUGUCAUUUGGUGCCACAAGCUUUCAGGGUAGACACUGAUUUUUCCCCCCUAAUAUCUGCUCUCUUUCAAAAGGAAUAAUUCAAAAGACUUAGGACAAUUACCACUGAAACACUUCGAGCUAUUUAGCUAAAGCCCACCAAACCAAAACAAAAUACUGAUUUUUUUUUUUUUUUUUGGUGACUCUGUUCAUACAGUGAAUAAAGAUCUAUCAAAGGAAAAGGAAACUGAGACCGAAAACUUAGGGUCUAAGUUGUUCUAAACCCAGGGUUCUCAAAUGUGUUGUACAAAAAGUUUCAUGUAAUAAAAUUAAGCAAAUAAAACAAAUGAAUAGAGGUCCAAAA